ACUUGCCGGAAGUGCCUUUCCAGUGGACCUGGGCUGUUGUUGCGGUUGUUUUCCUUCUCUCCGUGCAACGCUGGCAAGUCUCAAAGUCGCCACAGAAACAUGCCCCUGAUUCAGUGCCUCUGCUUAGCUGUAACAUGUUAAUCAGAACUACCUGGCAUCUUCCUGAACAAGACUUUCAAUAGGGGCCAGUAUGCUUCGCUUCAUCCAGAAGUUUUCUCAAGCAUCUUCAAAGAUACUGAAGUACUCUUUCCCAGUGGGACUAAGAACCAGCAGAACAGAUAUACUUUCUCUCAAGAUGUCUCUCCAGCAAAACUUUUCCCCAUGUCCAAGGCCUUGGCUUUCCUCAUCAUUUCCAGCGUAUAUGAGCAAGACACAGUGCUAUCAUACAUCCCCCUGCAGCUUUAAAAAGCAGCAGAAGCAAGCACUUCUAGCCAGACCCUCAAGCACCAUCACUUACCUAACUGACAGCCCAAAGCCAGCAUUAUGUGUAACUCUGGCAGGACUAAUCCCCUUCGUUGCUCCACCACUGGUCAUGCUGAUGACAAAAACUUAUAUUCCCAUAUUAGCUUUUACUCAGAUGGCUUAUGGAGCCAGUUUCCUAUCUUUCUUGGGUGGGAUCAGAUGGGGUUUUGCUCUACCAGAAGGUAGUCCAGCCAAACCAGACUACCUUAAUUUAGCUAGCAGUGCAGCUCCUCUUUUCUUUUCAUGGUUUGCCUUCCUUAUUUCUGAAAGACUUAGUGAAGCCAUAGUCACAGUAAUAAUGGGUAUGGGAGUAGCAUUCCACCUUGAACUUUUUCUCUUACCACAUUAUCCCAACUGGUUUAAAGCCCUGAGGAUAGUAGUCACUUUAUUGGCCACUUUUUCAUUUAUAAUCACUUUAGUAGUUAAAAGUAGUUUUCCAGAAAAAGGACAUAAGAGACCUGGUCAAGUAUAAAAAAUAUAAAAGUCUGGGAAGUGAGGAGCACCUCUGCCCAGCUGCUGCCCCGUCUGGGAAGUGAGGAGCGCCUCUGCCUGGCCGCCUGACCAUCUGGGAAGUGUGACAAGCGCCUCUGCCCGGCCGCUGUGCAACCUUCCACGUGUGAAGUGACAGCCUUGUGUGUGAUCUUUUCUGUCUUCCCCAAGUUUGCAUUUUCGACAUUAAAGUUUACUUUUUAGUUAAAAGUUUUAAAAAUAUAUAUAUAUAAAUACACUGUAGAUAACAUUUGUAUGCCAGCUACACCUUUUUCUACUUCUGUUUGGCUUUUUUUCCCCACACCAAUGGUAAUUUAUCUUCACAGAUUGUUCUUCAUUUCUAGAAAUUGUUACUUCAUGGUAAUUACUUGAGCAAAAGCUUGAAAAUCCCUGACAAGUACUUUUCAUCUCAUAGUAUAUUAGUUUUCACUCAGUCAUUUUAUGAAUAAUAUAGUUAUCCACUUAAACAUUUCAAUAUUUUAACCAUCUUGAAAAUUAAAGAUUAAAAAUCCCC